AGAUCUCGCGUGCGCUCGCCGCCCGGCGCAGCCCAGCCCGGCCCCCGCCUGGCGCCGCGAGCCGAGGUGUCUCCCGCGCCCGCGCCCGUGUCGCCGCCGUGCCCGCGAGCGGGAGCCGGAGUCGCCGCCGCCCGAGCGCAGCCGAGCGCACGCCGAGCCCGUCCGCCGCCGCCAUGGCCACCACGGUGACCUGCACCCGCUUCACCGACGAGUACCAGCUCUACGAGGAUAUUGGCAAGGGGGCUUUCUCUGUGGUCCGACGCUGUGUCAAGCUCUGCACCGGCCAUGAGUAUGCAGCCAAGAUCAUCAACACCAAGAAGCUGUCAGCCAGAGAUCACCAGAAGCUGGAGAGAGAGGCUCGGAUCUGCCGCCUUCUGAAGCAUUCCAACAUCGUGCGUCUCCACGACAGCAUCUCCGAGGAGGGCUUCCACUACCUGGUCUUCGAUCUGGUCACUGGUGGGGAGCUCUUUGAAGACAUUGUGGCGAGAGAGUACUACAGCGAGGCUGAUGCCAGUCACUGUAUCCAGCAGAUCCUGGAGGCCGUUCUCCAUUGUCACCAAAUGGGGGUCGUCCACAGAGACCUCAAGCCGGAGAACCUGCUUCUGGCCAGCAAGUGCAAAGGGGCUGCAGUGAAGCUGGCAGACUUCGGCCUAGCUAUCGAGGUGCAGGGGGACCAGCAGGCAUGGUUUGGUUUCGCUGGCACACCAGGCUACCUGUCCCCUGAGGUCCUUCGCAAAGAGGCGUAUGGCAAGCCUGUGGACAUCUGGGCAUGUGGGGUGAUCCUGUACAUCCUGCUCGUGGGCUACCCACCCUUCUGGGACGAGGACCAGCACAAGCUGUACCAGCAGAUCAAGGCUGGUGCCUAUGACUUCCCGUCCCCUGAGUGGGACACCGUCACUCCUGAAGCCAAAAACCUCAUCAACCAGAUGCUGACCAUCAACCCUGCCAAGCGCAUCACAGCCCAUGAGGCCCUGAAGCACCCGUGGGUCUGCCAACGCUCCACGGUAGCAUCCAUGAUGCACAGACAGGAGACUGUGGAGUGUCUGAAAAAGUUCAAUGCCAGGAGAAAGCUCAAGGGAGCCAUCCUCACCACCAUGCUGGCCACACGGAAUUUCUCAGUGGGCAGACAGACCACCGCUCCGGCCACAAUGUCCACCGCGGCCUCCGGCACCACCAUGGGGCUGGUGGAACAAGCCAAGAGUUUACUCAACAAGAAAGCAGAUGGAGUCAAGCCCCAGACGAAUAGCACCAAAAACAGUGCAGCCGCCACCAGCCCCAAAGGGACGCUUCCUCCUGCCGCCCUGGAGCCUCAAACCACCGUCAUCCAUAACCCAGUGGACGGGAUUAAGGAGUCUUCUGACAGUGCCAAUACCACCAUAGAGGAUGAAGACGCUAAAGCCCCCAGGGUCCCCGACAUCCUGAGCUCAGUGAGGAGGGGCUCGGGAGCCCCAGAAGCCGAGGGGCCCCUGCCCUGCCCAUCUCCGGCUCCCUUUAGCCCCCUGCCAGCCCCAUCCCCCAGGAUCUCUGACAUCCUGAACUCUGUGAGAAGGGGUUCAGGAACCCCAGAAGCCGAGGGCCCCCUCUCAGCGGGGCCCCCGCCCUGCCUGUCUCCGGCUCUCCUAGGCCCCCUGUCCUCCCCGUCCCCCAGGAUCUCUGACAUCCUGAACUCUGUGAGGAGGGGCUCAGGGACCCCAGAAGCCGAGGGCCCCUCGCCAGUGGGGCCCCCGCCCUGCCCAUCUCCGACUAUCCCUGGCCCCCUGCCCACCCCAUGGAUGGAUGACAUCCCAGGGCUGCUGCCACCCCCACCUGUGGGGAGACACCAGACUGGGGGUGGUGUGGAGAUACUCUUAGAGAAGAGGCUGCUGGGCCACGGGCUCGGCAUGGCAGGGCAGUGGCUAGCCCGGAAGCAGGAGAUCAUUAAGACCACGGAGCAGCUCAUCGAGGCCGUCAACAACGGUGACUUUGAGGCCUACGCGAAAAUCUGUGACCCAGGGCUGACCUCGUUUGAGCCUGAAGCACUGGGCAACCUGGUUGAAGGGAUGGACUUCCACAGAUUCUACUUCGAGAACCUGCUGGCCAAGAACAGCAAGCCGAUCCACACGACCAUCCUGAACCCACACGUGCACGUCAUUGGAGAGGAUGCCGCCUGCAUCGCUUACAUCCGGCUCACGCAGUACAUUGACGGGCAGGGCCGGCCCCGCACCAGCCAGUCUGAGGAGACCCGCGUGUGGCACCGCCGCGACGGCAAGUGGCAGAACGUGCACUUCCACUGCUCGGGCGCGCCUGUGGCCCCGCUGCAGUGAAGAGCUGCGCCCUGGUUUCGCCGGACAGAGUUGGUGUUUGGAGCCCGACUGCCCUCGGGCACACGGCCUGCCUGUCGCAUGUUUGUGUCUGCCUCGUUCCCUCCCCUGGUGCCUGUGUCUGCAGAAAAACAAGACCAGAUGUGAUUUGUUAAAAAAAAACAAAAAAAAAAAAAAAAAAAACAAGAUGACGACGACAACCACAAAAAAAAUUGACAUCAGAUGAAAUGAAAAAAAAAAAAAACAAAAAAAACUAAAGGAAGGAAAAAGCUGUAAAAAUCACUGGCAUUCGUGGGGCCACUCCCCACCCAAGCUCCACGUGUGUCCGUCUGUGCUCCUGGCCUCUGGGGGACCAGCUGGGACAUGAACUUGUCUGCCAGGCCCCCGUCGCGUGCUGAACGGUGUUAGUUUGUAGGUAACGCACACACCCCACACCUAAGGUGUCUGCAUCCUCCUGCCAACGCAUGGGCUCCACGUGGUGUGCUCGCUGGCUGUCGUGACUGUCAGCUGUCUCUUGGGAGGGGCUGUGGGGGCCCGCUGGGCUGCCUCCUUUCCCGCUAGUUGUGCCUGAGAGUUGCUGUUGUUCCUGCUUUCCCUUCCCUUCCUUUCAUCCCCUGAAGGGCUAGGUGUGGGUUUUCCGUGCCCGGUAUCCCCACACACCCAGCACGGACAACCCUUCGGCAGAGCCCAGGCCGGCCCCUCACCCCCUGGAGUAUUGAAACUGGAGUCCCGUCCCCAAGGCCUUCAGAGAUGCCCCUACACACCCAGGGCUCCAGCUCUGGUCCUUCUGGGGGAGUAAAGUGCAAAGAGGGGCACAGCUUAGUUUUGGGCCUCUCGCCGAGCAAGAGACAGCACUGCUGGCUACAGCUCCAACACAGCCAGCUGUGGCAAGAGGACUCUGCCUGGGCUGGCCCCCCUCCUGUGUGAGGUGUCUGUCCCUUCUCUGCUGGCCAGCAGCAGAUGCACUGGCAGCUCCCAACCCUGUUUCCGCCCCUCGGCCCUCCCCCAGCCUGUUCGGCUUCUCUGCAGCCCGCAAGGGGGAGCAGACUUUUGACAAAGGACUGCGGGCCUCGCUCAAGUCCCUGAGCCCCCAGCUGAAGCUGGGAGGGGAGGCCAGGCUUUGUGUCUGGGCAUAUUCGUCUGCUGAUGGGGUUUGGGGAAGCCUGGGGCUUGGGGUUUGGUCGGGUGGUGCAGCUAGUGGCAGAGCGGGAUCAGAGGUGGUGGCUGCCCAGCUUCUGGGCUGAGACAAGGGUCUGUGCAGGGGUUUACUGAAGUGGGAGUGCCUUUGGAAUCUGGGCCGGGAGCAGAAGGGAGCAAAAGCUACAGUGGGAGCCAGCCUAGGGCACAUGGGAGGCGUGAGGGCAGUGCUGCCCGUGCAGUGUCAGGUGUGCCAGUGCCUUGGCGGGCUGCAGUGCGUGUGAGGGCACCUUCUAGGUGGGCCAGGGAUGCAGCUAUGGAGAUAAGGCGGGCUGGGGACAGAAACAGGUGGGCACAGGGCCCAGGACACCAGCGGAUGGAGGGCAGGGUCUAGCCCUGUGCUCCUGAGCGUCGGCUGCCUGGGUUCGAGGCGGUGGGUCCCCGGCCCCUUGUGAUGGUGUGUACCAUGGGGGAGCUCGGGGACAGGGCAAGCCCGAGCAUGGUGGGGCUGCAGGGUGGGUCUGAAGCCAGGUUGGGUGGGGGUGGUCACAAGCCCUGACUGCAGAGGGUCAGGGGCUCCUGCCCCAGUGCCUGCCCACUUUCAAUUCACAUUGUUUUCAACAAGGAUUUUCUUUAUCUUCCCCUACAAAUCAAGCCAAGGGAGGGGCACAGAAUGGGGAACAGGACACAGGAUCCUAAACUCCAAGGGGACUGUCCACCGAUGAACACUCAGAGUGGACACCAUCUUCCGUCCACGCUGUGCCCAGGACAGCUGUCCCCAUCCAUGAACACAGGGUAAACAUCUGCCGGGCUCCGCACCAGUGGCUCCCUGGGCCAUGGGACAGCGGCAGGGCUCACCACGGACAGCACGUGGCCCAGCAGCCGGCCACCCUGGCGUCCUGGGGCCUCCUCCCCUCCUCUCCCUCUCACCUUGUCACCUCCACGGAGCUGCCUGUCUGGGAUAAUUUGGGGAUUUUUUUUCUGGGGGAUAAUUCUUUUGCAUGACCCCUAAAGAGCAAGCCACACCGGUCUGCUAGCUAGGUGUCCGCGGUGUGGUGGUGGCGGCCGCUGGCCAGCGCUGCAAGGGGUCGGCUGCCCACGGUGCUGGCUGGCCUCCCCUCCUCUCUCUUUUUGCUGAGUUUCAUUGUCUUUUCUUUCUGAGCCUUGUAAGUGUACAAAAAUUAUUCUUAUUUUGUUCUGUCUCGGGAAACUGCAAAUAAAAGAAAAACAGGACAAA